GCACACGUGGUCCGGCGUGGUUCAGGCGGGUGUCUUCGGCCGGGCUUGGGAACAUAAAAGUUUGUUUCACCACGUAAGCCGGACCUCGCACUCCGGUCCCGGUCUCGUCGCCAAGAUGGUGAAGCCCAAGUACAAAGGACGGAGCACCAUCAACCCGUCCAAGGCCAGCACAAACCCAGAUCGAGUGCAGGGAGCAGGAGGCCAAAACAUGAGGGACCGGGCCACCAUCCGGCGCCUGAAUAUGUAUAGGCAAAAGGAGCGCAGGAACAGUCGUGGUAAAAUAAUUAAACCCCUGCAAUAUCAAUCAACGGUGGCUUCUGGCACAGUGGCAAGAGUAGAGCCAAAUAUUAAAUGGUUUGGAAACACACGUGUGAUUAAGCAGUCAUCAUUACAAAAAUUUCAAGAGGAAAUGGAUACAGUUAUGAAGGAUCCAUACAAAGUUGUCAUGAAGCAAAGCAAGUUACCAAUGUCUCUUCUCCAUGAUCGAAUCCGGCCUCAUAACUUGAAGGUGCACAUUCUUGAUACUGAAAGUUUUGAAACUACAUUUGGCCCUAAGUCACAGAGGAAACGACCAAACUUAUUUGCAAGUGAUAUGCAGUCUCUUAUCGAAAAUGCUGAAAUGUCCACUGAGAGCUAUGACCAGGGCAAGGAUCGUGAUUUGGUAACUGAAGACACUGGUGUGAGAAAUGAAGCUCAAGAAGAGAUCUAUAAAAAGGGACAGUCCAAAAGAAUAUGGGGUGAGCUCUACAAGGUGAUAGAUUCAUCAGAUGUUGUAGUUCAAGUUCUUGAUGCUAGAGAUCCAAUGGGUACUCGUUCCCCUCACAUUGAAACUUACCUGAAGAAGGAAAAACCUUGGAAACACCUCAUUUUUGUACUUAACAAAUGUGACCUUGUUCCAACCUGGGCAACAAAACGGUGGGUUGCUGUCCUCUCCCAGGAUUAUCCAACACUUGCUUUCCAUGCAAGCCUUACUAACCCGUUUGGCAAGGGAGCAUUCAUUCAGCUUCUGCGGCAGUUUGGAAAGCCCUGGCACCUGACGUUCCACGCUCUGCUGGGCUUUCCAGGCCUGCUGUGCAUCCUCUGCCCAUGGAGCCCAUGCAGCUUCUAUGUCCUCUGGUUGGAGAGGGCCCUGCCAAAAUUCAAGCUUCAGAUCCCUGGUCAGACGUCAGCUCCUGAGGGAAGCCGUGGAACCAGACUACCCUAUCAAAUUCUUAAAGCUUCAUGUUCUUUGCACACUGACAAGAAACAGAUCAGUGUUGGGUUCAUUGGCUAUCCAAAUGUUGGCAAGAGCUCUGUGAUAAAUACAUUGCGUUCUAAGAAAGUUUGCAACGUGGCUCCCAUUGCAGGUGAAACAAAGGUCUGGCAGUAUAUUACUUUGAUGCGUCGGAUAUUCCUGAUUGACUGUCCAGGUGUGGUUUACCCCUCUGAGGACUCCGAGACAGACAUUGUGCUAAAAGGAGUUGUUCAAGUAGAAAAAAUUAAGAGUCCUGAAGACCACAUUGGUGCUGUACUUGAACGAGCAAAGCCAGAAUAUAUCAGCAAAACAUACAAGAUUGAUUCUUGGGAGAAUGCUGAGGACUUUCUUGAGAAGCUCGCUUUCCGGACUGGGAAGUUACUAAAGGGUGGAGAGCCCGACUUGCAGACUGUGGGUAAGAUGGUCCUCAAUGACUGGCAGAGGGGCCGGAUUCCUUUCUUUGUCAAGCCACCCAAUGCAGAGCCACUUGUGGCCCCCCAGCUUCUACCCUCCUCAUCUUUGGAAGUUGUCCCAGAAGCAGCCCAGAACAAUCCAGGGGAGGAAGUCACAGAAACUGCAGGUGAAGGGUCAGAAUCCAUCAUUAAGGAAGAAACAGAAGAGAACAGUCACUGUGAUGCUAACACAGAGAUGCAGCAGAUUCUCACACGAGUUCGGCAGAACUUUGGUAAAAUCAACGUGGUGCCUCAGUUUUCUGGGGAUGACCUGGUUCCUGUGGAGGUGUCAGAUCUUGAGGAAGAGCUUGAGAGCUUUUCUGAUGAAGAGGAGGAGGAACAGGAGCAACAAAGAGAUGAUGCGGAAGAGUCUUCCUCGGAGCCUGAGGAGGAAAAUGUGGGAAACGACACCAAAGCCGUUAUUAAAGCACUGGAUGAGAAGAUUGCCAAAUAUCAGAAGUUUCUAGACAAAGCCAAAGCCAAAAAGUUUUCAGCAGUCAGAAUAUCCAAGGGACUGAGUGAAAAGAUAUUUGCAAAACCUGAAGAACAAAGAAAAACACUGGAAGAAGAUGUAGAUGACAGAGCACCUUCCAAAAAGGGAAAGAAGCGGAAGGCACAAAGGGAAGAGGAACAGGAACAUUCAAAUAAAGCUCCCAGGGCGCUUACAUCAAAAGAACGGAGGCGAGCAGUACGACAGCAACGGCCGAAAAAAGUUGGUGUGCGCUACUAUGAAACACACAACGUGAAAAAUAGGAACAGGAACAAAAAGAAGACCAAUGACUCAGAGGGACAGAAACACAAACGCAAAAAAUUCAGACAAAAGCAGUAAUGUUUAAAAGGUUUUUAUUAAAUUAUACAAAAACAGGCA